UUAAAAUUACUCCGUCUCAGGUAUUUUGUUACAGCAGCACAUGGGGACUGAGACUGGGUGUGCAGGUGGUGGAGGAGGGUGUGCAGGUGUGUUUGAGGGUGUUUGCCUCAAUCUUUAGACAGCAUCAGGGCCACAAUACCUGCAGGUGUCAGGACGUUAACUGCAGACAUUGGUGAAUAAAAGCCAGUUGUCCUGAGUUUGGCAAGAAAACCUUUGGAAGAGGCCUCACAAGCCACUCCAGGCUACAAGACGGGGCGUUUGUCCUGGGGGACCUGCCGUCACCCUUAGUGGUCCAGCAGCACCGUCUCAGCCUCUCUGGCCAGAGCAGCUGCCCCGCAGGGGCCCCCGAGUCCUGGAGAGCUCUGUCAGACAAGAUGUCCAUGGGCAGCAGACCUCUGGCCACUGCAGGCUCCAGGCACCAGAGUGAGACCCAGCAGGCUUCAGCCGGCAAGAGGGCCCCUGACUGUGGACGACUCCCUCACGGUGGUGGUCUUGGAGGGACCCCUGCUAACAGAAAGGGUGCAUCCCUGUCCAGCUUCCCGUCCUCACCCCCAAAGUCAGCGUCAGCAGCUGGCCCGCAUCGGAGGCAUUCAGAUAGGAGUCCUUGGGGACCCCCCCCAACCGACACGAACUGGAAAUGCCUUGAGUACUGAGGGAGGAGGGCUGCAGGGACAGGAGGGAGGAUGUCCUUAAACACACUUGCUGGCCCUUCUCAGGAGAAACCCUUCCUUGUCAUGGGUCGUGGUGAAGCUGUGCUCCGAGUUAAGCCAGUGACCGAAUUCCUGAGCUCAGAGGAUGGCCAGUGAAACAACUUGCUAAAAUGCUGAGACUCCCUGCACUCGCGAGACUACGAAAACACGUGCUGAAGUCAGUGAGAGCCACGGUGGCCAAAGUCUUUGCUCAGAACCAGCUGCGCAGAUGGACACCCGCUCCGGGAGCCAGUGUUCCGUCACCCCAGAAGCCAUACUCAAUAAUGAAAAGCUGGUCUUGCCGCCCCGCAUCUCCAGAGUGAACGGCUGGUCGUUACCCCUGCACUACUUCCAGGUGGUGACCUGGGCUGUCUUCGUGGGCCUUUCCUCGGCCACCUUCGGGAUCUUCAUUCCCUUCCUGCCUCACGCGUGGAAAUACAUUGCCUACGUGGUGACCGGGGGGAUCUUCUCGUUCCACCUCGUCGUCCACCUGAUCGCGUCCUGCAUCGACCCGGCCGACUCCAAUGUCAGACUCAUGAAGAACUAUUCUCAGCCCAUGCCCCUCUUCGACAGAUCAAAACAUGCACACGUGAUCCAGAAUCAGUUCUGCCACCUGUGCAAGGUCACCGUGCCUCAACACCCUCCCCCAGCCUCCCAUUCCCUGCUGGACGCCCUCUCCCCAGGCCGCACAGGGCUGGUUCCUCCGAGGCACCUGGCUUCCAGUGAUGGACCUCUGGCCCUGCCCCAACCUGCGCACUUGGGGCCUGACAGGCGUUCCCCGAUUCAUCCCUCCAGGAACAAGAAAACCAAACACUGCAUUUCCUGCAAUAAGUGUGUGUCCGGCUUCGACCACCACUGCAAAUGGAUCAACAACUGCGUGGGAAGCCGGAAUUAUUGGUUCUUCUUCAGCACUGUGGCCUCGGCCACAGCUGGCAUGCUCUGCCUGAUCGCCAUCCUGCUGUAUGUCCUCGUCCAGUACCUCGUGAACCCCGGGGUGCUCCGCACGGACCCCAGGUAUGAAGAUGUCAAGAAUAUGAACACGUGGCUGCUGUUCCUCCCCCUGUUCCCGGUGCAGGUGCAGACCCUGAUAGUCGUGAUCAUCGGGAUGCUCGUGCUCCUGCUGGACUUUCUUGGCUUGGUGCACCUGGGCCAGCUGCUCAUCUUCCACAUCUACCUGAGGUCAGCCUCUCCCAGAAGUGAGAUCAUGGACAAAAAGGGCAAAUCACAGGAAGAAAUUAAAUCCAUGAGGACCCAGCAGGCCCAGCAAGAAGCUGAACUCACGCCGAGACCUGCAGGAGUGGUGCCAGAGGCCAAGAAGAUGACCACCUUUGAGUAUCUCAUUAAUAACCGCAAAGAAGAGAGUUCAAAACAUCAAGCAGUGAGGAAAGAUCCAUACGUGCAAAUGGACAAAGGAGUUCUCCAGCAAGGAGCUGGCGCCCUGGGCUCAUCUGCACAGGGAGUCAAAGCCAAGAGCUCCCUGCUGAUUCACAAGCACUUAUGUCACUUCUGCACUUCAGUAAACCAGGAUGGGGAUUCGACGGCACGGGAAGGGGAUGAAGACCCGUGUCCAUCUGCACUUGGAGCCAAGGCCAGGAACUCCCGGCUGAUUUGCAGGCGCCUGUGUCAGUUCUCCACUCGUGUACACCCAGACGGGGGCUCGAUGGCACAGGAAGCAGAUGAUGCCCCGAGUAUAUCUACACUUGGGCUGCAACAAGAAACAACAGAGCCCAUGAAAACUGACAGUGCUGAAAGUGAAGACUGAGAUUCAGGAGCUCAGGUGCCCCUGUGAUCCAGGUCUUCUACCCUGAAACCCCACCCUCCAUCAAGGUCCUGCCUGUAGAGUCUACCUUGCAAAGCCUCCUGCUCCUACCCAUGCUACAGGCCAGGAACCAGAGCCCAUCAUCUCAGAGGCCCCUGGAUGUCCUUCGAAGGAACCAGGACCCUCAGAGCCCAGCAUCCAUCUCUGUCAUCAUCUUCAUCACACCCAAAGAAGAGCCAGCCUUGCAGGAGGGUUUACAUCUCCAGGAAGAUGGGCUGCCAGCAACUGCAGAGGAUGCAGCCACCUGCUUAACUGUGCUGUCCAGCCAGCCAGCCAGCUGCAGGGCCUCUUGCUGCUUAAGAGCUGAUGGGCCGGGCAUGUUGGCUCACACCUGUGAGCACAGUACUGGGAAAUGGGAGCACAGUACUAGGAAAUGGGAGCACAGUACUGGGAAAUGGGAGCACAGUACUGGGAAAUGGGGGCUCACAGCACUGCAAAAUGGGAGCACAGUAUUGGGAAAUGGGAGCACAGUACUGGGAAGUGGGAGCACAGUACUGAGAAGUGGGAGCACAGUACUGAGAAAUGGGAGUACACUACUGAGAAAUGGGAGCACAGUACUGGGAAAUGGGCAUACAGUACUGAGAAAUGGGAGCACACAGUACUGGGAAAUGGGAGCACAGUACUGGGAAAUGGGAGCCCACAGUACUGGGAAAGGGGAGUUCACAGUACUCGGAAAUGGGAGCAUAGUACUGGGAAAUGGGAGCACAGUACUGGGAAAUGGGAGCAUAGUACUGGGAAACCCCAGACCUGGAUUCUGAGUUUUUCAGCCUAGCCCAGACUUCUUAUCUUAGUAGACAAAAAGAGUCAAUACCAGAGAACCAGAGGCAUCCUCUGUAUUUUAAUGAACUCUGCAUUUUAAUCUGUUUAGUAGUCAUUUUUUAAAAGAUAAUCAGUUUUCCAAAUAUAUCUAUAAGUUACUACGUGCA